CUUCUUUUCGCCGGAGUUGAAUCUGUGCUGCCCGUGUCCAGGUGCUGGGCUUCCGGACCGACACGGAUCCCCCAUCCCCGCCCGCGGUCGCCUUGUCAUGCUGCCCAAAGUGGAGACGGAAGCCCUGGGACUGGCUCGAUCGCAUGGGGAACAGGGCCAGAUGCCGGAAAACAUGCAAGGUAAGGAGGCGCCGCGCGGCGCUCCGGCUCCCGCUGCUUCCCCACCCCCGGGCUCGCCCUGCAGGCUUCAGCCUCCCGCCCCGCGCGGGCGCGGGAGUAGCCCCGCUGGGCGCUCGCAGCCGCGGGAGUCAAGCCCCCUCCCCAGGUGCAGGCAUAAAAGUUUAUGGCUCUUGAACAAUGCGGGGCAGAGGUUUUUCCAAGCAACGUCUAAUUGGCCGCUUCUAAUUAAGGAAAGAGAGGCUUCCAGCUCUAUGGCAACCCAAGCAGGGCAGCUUCAGGCUAAAGGUACUUUAGAAUAAUAAGAUCAUUCUAAGAAAUGGAAUGUCUCACUGGACACCCGAACAGGUUCUCUGUCAUUGGAAUUGGUGUGUACUGUACUUCAACCAGUACUCUUGUGUGGAGGGAGGCGACCCAGUCUAGGAAAGUCAACUACAGAAAGAGGUGACCUCCGAAAGGAUUGUCUUAGCGCUAUUAGAAUACAUGUGACCACACCAAAAGCCCAGGCGGACACCCGCAGCCAGCUCGGAUUUGGACAAUUCAACAUUGCUGGCAGAACUGAAGGGAACAAGUUACCCCAACCCCAUCCCCUGUACGCGUAGUGCUGAGUGAGUUGGGGGUGGGAGGACAGCGGUUCGUUUAUUGCCCCCUUUUAAAAUCUGAGAUCUGAAAAUAUGGAGGUCCCAUUCGUUUUCCCAGCUCUUGAUUGCCAACAAAAAAACAAAUCCCGCUGGCUACAUUUUCUCCUCAUUCCAAAAUAGCAACCCUAUGGCUUGUAUUAAGCCCUUCAGAAGUUUAUCUCAUUUGCUCUGGGCCAGGGAGGGAACAAUGCUAGGAAAAGUCACCGGUGCUCUUCCAUCCUCGCCCCUUCCAGGGUGCAGGAUGUGCGGGCCGGCGGGCCUGUGAUCCCGGAACGCUUCCUGCCAUCCCCUUGCGCGAACUUGAAAGGACUGGGAGGUGUUGAGAGCAGAGUUCAGGGCUGGUGCACUCUGCGGUGCUGAGUGGGCGGCGCGCCCGGGCGCUCAGGCCGGGGGACCUGUAGUCGCCCUACCGCGGAGGGGAAAAUACGUAGCUGGAGGGCGUGCGCCGUGCGGGUUGUGAUCCGUUACCCCAUCGGUCAUCCUGGGGUCUCCCCAAGCCUCUAGGUAGGGCUGUGAGAGUCCCCUAGAGCUGAAGCCCCGGAGGCUGACCUGUGGGUCUGGCUGCUAUGGGAACCCGGUUGGUCCAAAGAAGCCUUUCUUCCGGGCACCUGGAAUUCCAGUUUAGUGUGGGGCAUCGGGGAAGUGGCGCUGGGGGGCUGGGUUGGGGGACCUCAGCCGGCAGCUCCGGAGAGGGCCUACCCUUGGGGUCGCUGGGUGAGGCCGGCACGAUUCUUGGCUCCAAAAGGAAAGUUUCUGCUUCUUGUUCUGGCGCGAGAAGCCAAAGACUUAUUUUGAGAGCGGAGAGAGAAAUGUUAUUGGUAACGUUUUCUUUGGAAAGUUCGAGAGGGGUCUUCUGGACACACUACCUAGUGCCCCCAAACCAGAGAAGUAGUUUUUCUUUGGUGCCUGGGCUCAGAAGUCGCCACUCACUCAGCCCAUGGUUCGAAAUCAGCAUGGGAAGCGCCGGGGCAAGGCUUCGUCGGAGACUAGAGGCCUGCCUGUCGGGAGGAGCCCCUGGGGGAUGGGGACCCCAUUCUCCUGCUUGCUCUGGUUCCCACCUGGGACGCCUCCGUAGGAGCCCAGAAAGACGAUCCACUACAUGGUCCCGGGACAGAGCAGCGCGCCCAACUUUGAGGGAACUUUGUGCGCCUCUCUGAGGCCCUAGCUUUCCAAGGCACCGCCGUCCGUUCUUCUUUCCCUAGACCGAAACUGGGGAAGAGUGUGGGCGCUUCUUUGCCCCGAUGAGUUCGCCUCCCCAAACGCCUACUUCGGCUGCACCAGAGCAUCUGGGAAACUCUGAAAGGUGCCCAGGCCUCACACAGCAGCGUCUCCCUACUCAGCCUCUGUCUUUGGGUUUUUUCAAGAGAGUCUCUACCUCAUGCCUCGGUCUUUCUUCGAUGUCGGGUCCCCGAGUGUCUCAAUUUAAAAUGGUGAAUUACUCCUAUGAUGAAGAUCUGGAAGAGCUUUGUCCCGUGUGUGGAGAUAAAGUGUCUGGGUACCAUUAUGGGCUCCUCACCUGUGAAAGCUGCAAGGGAUUUUUUAAGCGAACAGUCCAAAAUAAUAAAAGGUACACAUGUAUAGAAAACCAGAACUGCCAAAUUGACAAAACACAGAGAAAGCGUUGUCCUUACUGUCGUUUUCAAAAAUGUCUAAGUGUUGGAAUGAAGCUAGAAGCUGUAAGGGCCGACCGAAUGCGUGGAGGAAGGAAUAAGUUUGGGCCAAUGUACAAGAGAGACAGGGCCCUGAAGCAACAGAAAAAAGCCCUCAUCCGAGCCAAUGGACUUAAGCUAGAAGCCAUGUCUCAGGUGAUCCAAGCUAUGCCCUCUGACCUGACCAUUUCCUCUGCAAUUCAAAACAUCCACUCUGCCUCCAAAGGCCUACCUCUGAACCAUGCUGCCUUGCCUCCUACAGACUAUGACAGAAGUCCCUUUGUAACAUCCCCCAUUAGCAUGACAAUGCCCCCUCACGGCAGCCUGCAAGGUUACCAAACAUAUGGCCACUUUCCUAGCCGGGCCAUCAAGUCUGAGUACCCAGACCCCUAUACCAGCUCACCCGAGUCCAUAAUGGGCUAUUCAUAUAUGGAUAGUUACCAGACGAGCUCUCCAGCAAGCAUCCCACAUCUGAUACUGGAACUUUUGAAGUGUGAGCCAGAUGAGCCUCAAGUCCAGGCUAAAAUCAUGGCCUAUUUGCAGCAAGAGCAGGCUAACCGAAGCAAGCACGAAAAGCUGAGCACCUUUGGGCUUAUGUGCAAAAUGGCAGAUCAAACUCUCUUCUCCAUUGUCGAGUGGGCCAGGAGUAGUAUCUUCUUCAGAGAACUUAAGGUUGAUGACCAAAUGAAGCUGCUUCAGAACUGCUGGAGUGAGCUCUUAAUCCUCGACCACAUUUACCGACAAGUGGUACAUGGAAAGGAAGGAUCCAUCUUCCUGGUUACUGGGCAACAAGUGGACUAUUCCAUAAUAGCAUCACAAGCCGGAGCCACCCUCAACAACCUCAUGAGUCAUGCACAGGAGUUAGUGGCAAAACUUCGUUCUCUCCAGUUUGAUCAACGAGAGUUCGUAUGUCUGAAAUUCUUGGUGCUCUUUAGUUUAGAUGUCAAAAACCUUGAAAACUUCCAGCUGGUAGAAGGUGUCCAGGAACAAGUCAAUGCCGCCCUGCUGGACUACACAAUGUGUAACUACCCGCAGCAGACAGAGAAAUUUGGACAGCUACUUCUUCGACUACCCGAAAUCCGGGCCAUCAGUAUGCAGGCUGAAGAAUACCUCUACUACAAGCACCUGAACGGGGAUGUGCCCUAUAAUAACCUUCUCAUUGAAAUGUUGCAUGCCAAAAGAGCAUAAGUUACAACCCCUAGGAGCUCUGCUUUCAAAACAAAAAGAGAUUGGGGGAGUGGGGAGGGGGAAGAAGAACAGGAAGAAAAAAAGUACUCUGAACUGCUCCAAGUAACGCUAAUUAAAAACUUGCUUUAAAGAUAUUGAAUUUAAAAAGGCAUAAUAAUCAAAUACUUAAUAGCAAAUAAAUGAUGUAUCAGGGUAUUUGUAUUGCAAACUGUGAAUCAAAGGCUUCACAGCCCCAGAGGAUUCCAUAUAAAAGACAUUGUAAUGGAGUGGAUUGAACUCACAGAUGGAUACCAACACGGUCAGAAGAAAAACGGACAGAACGGUUCUUGUAUAUUUAAACUGAUCUCCACUAUGAAGAAAUUUAGGAACUAAUCUUAUUAAUUAGGCUUAUACAGCGGGGGAUUUGAGCUUACAGGAUUCCUCCAUGGUAAAGCUGAACUGAAACAAUUCUCAAGAAUGCAUCAGCUGUACCUACAAUAGCCCCUCCCUCUUCCUUUGAAGGCCCCAGCACCUCUGCCCUGUGGUCACCGAAUCUGUACUAAGGACCUGUGUUCAGCCACACCCAGUGGUAGCUCCACCAAAUCAUGAACAGCCUAAUUUUGAGUGUCUGUGUCUUAGACCUGCAAACAGCUAAUAGGAAAUUCUAUUAAUAUGUUAGCUUGCCAUUUUAAAUAUGUUCUGAGGGUUGUUUUGUCUCGUGUUCAUGAUGUUAAGAAAAUGCAGGCAGUAUCCCUCAUCUUAUGUAAGUGUUAAUUAAUAUUAAGGGAAAUGACUACAAACUUUCAAAGCAAAUGCUCCAUAGCUAAAGCAACUUAGACCUUAUUUCUGCUACUGUUGCUGAAAUGUGGCUUUGGCAUUGUUGGAUUUCAUAAAAAAUUUCUGGCAGGAAGUCUUGUUAGUAUACAUCAGUCUUUUUCAUCAUCCAAGUUUGUAGUUCAUUUAAAAAUACAACAUUAAACACAUUUUGCUAGGAUGUCAAAUAGUCACAGUUCUAAGUAGUUGGAAACAAAAUUGACGCAUGUUAAUCUAUGCAAAGAGAAAGGAAAGGAUGAGGUGAUGUAUUGACUCAAGGUUCAUUCUUGCUGCAAUUGAACAUCCUCAAGAGUUGGGAUGGAAAUGGUGAUUUUUACAUGUGUCCUGGAAAGAUAUUAAAGUAAUUCAAAUCUUCCCCAAAGGGGAAAGGAAGAGAGUGAUACUGACCUUUUUAAGUCAUAGACCAAAGUCUGCUGUAGAACAAAUAUGGGAGGACAAAGAAUCGCAAAUUCUUCAAAUGACUAUUAUCAGUAUUAUUAACAUGCGAUGCCACAGGUAUGAAAGUCUUGCCUUAUUUCACAAUUUUAAAAGGUAGCUGUGCAGAUGUGGAUCAACAUUUGUUUAAAAUAAAGUAUUAAUACUUUAAAGUCAAAUAAGAUAUAGUGUUUACAUUCUUUAGGUCCUGAGGGGCAGGGGGAUCUGUGAUAUAACAAAAUAGCAAAAGCGGUAAUUUCCUUAAUGUUAUUUUUCUGAUUGGUAAUUAUUUUUAACAGUACUUAAUUAUUCUAUGUCGUGAGACACUAAAAUCAAAAACGGGAAUCUCAUUUAGACUUUAAUUUUUUUGAGAUUAUCGGCGGCACAAUCACUUUGUAGAAACUGUAAAAAAUAAAAGUAUCUCCUAGUCCCUUAAUUUUUUCAUAAAUAUUUCUGGCUUUUGAGUAGUGUAUUUAUAUUGUAUAUCAUACUUUCAACUGUAGACAAUUAUGAUGCUAAUUUAUUGUUUCUUGGUUUCACCUUUGUAUAAGAUAUAGCCAAGACUGAAGAAACCAAAUAUAUGUGUUUACUGUAGCAUGUCUUCAAAUUAGUGGAACUUAGUUCAGGGACAUAGAAGAGUCUUAAUGAAUUAAAAUCAUUCACUUGAUUAAAUGUCUGUAAAUCUUCAUCAUUCCUACUGUAGUUUAUUUAAUAUCUAUUGUAAAUUAUGUGACUUGUAGCUUCCUCUGGUUUUCAAGUAAACUCAACAAGGUGGAGUCUUACCUGGUUUUCCUUUCCAAGCAUUGUAAAUUGUAUACCAAAGAUAUUAGUUAUUACUUCUGUGUGUACAAAGAGGAUUAUUUUAUUAUGUUUAUUAAUCACCUCUAAUACUCAUCCACAUGAAGGGUACACAUUAGGUAAGCUGGGCGUUGACUCAUGCGCAGUCUCAGUCACCCGUGUUAUCUUCGUGGCUCAAAGGACAAUGCAAAAUCGCCGAUCAGAGCUCAUACCCAAAGCAUUACAGAGAACAGCAGCAUCAUUGCCCUCCCCAGCUGAAAAACAAGUUGGCUAGAAGAUACAUGGAGAGGAAUGGUGUGGUCAACAGUUAAUGAAACGGUUCUAUCAUGCAUGUGUAAUGUGGAUGGAGACAAUUAUAAGAUUUGACUAUAACUAUUUGGAGGGUCUUUAACAUUGCCAAAAAAACAAAUAUGUUGAUUUUUAUUUUAUUUUAUUUUUUAUUUUAAGAGGCGGGAUCUUGAUCUCACAUGUUGCCCAGGCUGGCCUUGAACUCCUGGGCUCAAGCAUUCCUCCUGCCUCAGCCUCCCCCAUAGCUGGGACUAGGGGUGCAUGCCAGCAUACCUGGCUACGUUGACUCUUAAAAUCUAUGUUCUCUUAUUUUAAAGAUACAGUGCUCCCCACUGAAAAUUAAACCUAAAAAAUGUCACAUAUUGGUAUGUUGUUAACCUGGUAGAUUAAAUCAUGAGAAUGAUUAGAAAGACGGGCAACACAGCGGGUUACAUCCACACUGCUGAUCACACCAACGACAGGAGCUGAUAAGCAAGAAAGCGUCACAGCCAGCGUCUGUUCACCCAAGGUUGACAAGUGAAGUUUCUCUAAUGUUGAUUGUUAGCCGAUUUGUAACCUGGCAUUUACUUAGCAACUGCCUUAUCAAUUACAGGAUUUGCCGGUAAAAGCAGACUCAAAUAUAAAGGUUUUUGGCUUAACUUGGUUUAUUAUAGUUGCUCUAUGUUUGUAAACAGACAAUCUCUAAUGUCUGAUUAUUUGUAUCACAGAUCUGCAGCUGCCUUGGACUUGAAUCCAUGCAAUGUUUAGAGUGUGAAGUCAGUUACUUGUUGAUGUUUUCUUACUGUAUCAAUGAAAUACAUAUUGUCAUGUCAGUUCUUGCCAGGAACUUCUCAACAAAAUGGAAUUUUUUUUUUCAGUAUUUCAAUAAAUAUUGAUAUGCCCAGCCUGAUAA